AGAAAGAGAUUACCAGCCACAGACGGGUCAUGAGCGCGGUAUUACUGCUGGCCCUCCUGGGGUUCAUCCUCCCACUGCCAGGAGUGCAGGCGCUGCUCUGCCAGUUUGGGACAGUUCAGCAUGUGUGGAAGGUGUCCGACCUGCCCCGGCAAUGGACCCCUAAGAACACCAGCUGCGACAGCGGCUUGGGGUGCCAGGACACGUUGAUGCUCAUUGAGAGCGGACCCCAAGUGAGCCUGGUGCUCUCCAAGGGCUGCACGGAGGCCAAGGACCAGGAGCCCCGCGUCACUGAGCACCGGAUGGGCCCCGGCCUCUCCCUGAUCUCCUACACCUUCGUGUGCCGCCAGGAGGACUUCUGCAACAACCUCGUUAACUCCCUCCCGCUUUGGGCCCCACAGCCCCCAGCAGACCCAGGAUCCUUGAGGUGCCCAGUCUGCUUGUCUAUGGAAGGCUGUCUGGAGGGGACAACAGAAGAGAUCUGCCCCAAGGGGACCACACACUGUUAUGAUGGCCUCCUCAGGCUCAGGGGAGGAGGCAUCUUCUCCAAUCUGAGAGUCCAGGGAUGCAUGCCCCAGCCAGUUUGCAACCUGCUCAAUGGGACACAGGAAAUUGGGCCCGUGGGUAUGACUGAGAACUGCGAUAUGAAAGAUUUUCUGACCUGUCAUCGGGGGACCACCAUUAUGACACACGGAAACUUGGCUCAAGAACCCACUGAUUGGACCACAUCGAAUACCGAGAUGUGCGAGGUGGGGCAGGUGUGUCAGGAGACGCUGCUGCUCCUAGAUGUAGGACUCACAUCAACCCUGGUGGGGACAAAAGGCUGCAGCACUGUUGGGGCUCAAAAUUCCCAGAAGACCACCAUCCACUCAGCCCCUCCUGGGGUGCUUGUGGCCUCCUAUACCCACUUCUGCUCCUCGGACCUGUGCAAUAGUGCCAGCAGCAGCAGCGUUCUGCUGAACUCCCUCCCUCCUCAAGCUGCCCCUGUCCCAGGAGACCGGCAGUGUCCUACCUGUGUGCAGCCCCUUGGAACCUGUUCAAGUGGCUCCCCCCGAAUGACCUGCCCCAGGGGCGCCACUCAUUGUUAUGAUGGGUACAUUCAUCUCUCAGGAGGUGGGCUGUCCACCAAAAUGAGCAUUCAGGGCUGCGUGGCCCAACCUUCCAGCUUCUUGUUGAACCACACCAGACAAAUCGGGAUCUUCUCUGCGCGUGAGAAGCGUGAUGUGCAGCCUCCUGCCUCUCAGCAUGAGGGAGGUGGGGCUGAGGGCCUGGAGUCUCUCACUUGGGGGGUGGGGCUGGCACUGGCCCCAGCGCUGUGGUGGGGAGUGGUUUGCCCUUCCUGCUAACUCUAUUACCCCCACGAUUCUUCACCGCUGCUGACCACCCACACUCAACCUCCCUCUGACCUCAUAACCUAAUGGCCUUGGACACCAGAUUCUUUCCCAUUCUGUCCAUGAAUCAUCUUCCCCACACACAAUCAUUCAUAUCUACUCACCUAACAGCAACACUGGGGAGAGCCUGGAGCAUCCGGACUUGCCCUAUGGGAGAGGGGACGCUGGAGGAGUGGCUGCAUGUAUCUGAUAAUACAGACCCUGUCCUUUCUCCCAGUGCUGGGAUUUCUCCAUGUGAGGGGGCAGCAGGACACCCAGGGAUCUAGCGUGGGGGAGGAGAGGAGCCUAAUGAGAAAAUGACCAUCUAAAGCCUGCCCUUCAUUGGUCUGGUUCACGUCUCCAAACCAGCUUGGAUGGUAGCAGAGACUUCAGGGUGCUCCAGCCAAACGUAUUUGGGCAUCACCAUGACCUGGGAGGGGAAGAUGCACUGAGACGUAUGAGGCUUCCAGCCUAGCAGCCAGGGCCCUAGCACAAACAGGAGGCUCGCCCCAUCUGAGCAACUGCAGGAGAGGUUAGUACAGUCAUGCAUUGCUUAACGACAGGGACGUGUCGUUAGAAAUGUGUCGUUAGGUGAUUUUAUGACCAUAGGAACAUUGUAGCGUGCACUUACACCAACCCAGAUGGUACAGCCCAAUACACACCCAGGAUGGACGCUAGAGUCGACUGCUCCUAGGCUACAAGCCUGCAGUGCAUGUUAUGGUGUGAAUACUGCAGGCAAUCUUAACACCACGGCAAGUAUUUGUGCAUCUACACACAUCUAAACAUAGAAAAGGUACAGCAUAAAUACACUAUUGUCAUCUCAGCAGA